AGUAUAUUAUAAAGCAGCACUGAGCCGGCUGCCAAGGCAGGGCUGAAUCCCAACUGGAGUGGUGUGUAAGGCUCAGAGAAUUAUGUCUUGAAUUCUGCCACACCACCCGUCGCUGAAAUCUCAUCUGGUGUGUUCCCUGAACCAGCGCUGGCCUUCUGGUUCCUGUCUGCCCACUCCGCUCCCUCUCCUUCCCUCUCCCUCCCUCCGUCCCUGCCUUUAUUUACUCAUGGAGGGUGGAGCCCGGCUCGAUCUGAGUCAGGGCCAGGGAACCAAUCAGAGGUGCUCUGGGGCAUUCCAGGGGCCAAAAUUCAUGAUCCCUUUUGGAAAAGAAUUUCCCAAAAAGAUCCCUGGCAUCACAGUGUUGUGACUGCACCUUCCUCAGUUCCUGUGCAGUGAGCCUUCACCGCCCCCACACCCCACCGCCCUAUCAGCUUUUCCUCUGUCUCCCCCACCAGGGACUGGAGGGCGAAAGAGCCCUGUCUGAUGGAGACUUCUUCCCCUUGAGAAUCUUUUGUAUGUAAGUAUAAAGAUGCACAUAUCACUUUAAAAGAGCACUCGGCAGCCUUUUCUGGGAGCAUCUUUAGGGUAGGGAACUUGAGGGAUUUUGUUCGUCUCCUAGAACCUGUGGCCCUUCCUCUUUAGUCCUCACAUAAGUGGUCCCAGAAAUUGCAGUUACCAGGUGUCUGCCUCUGGAAAUGGCCCGUGCCCAGCCUCUCCCACGGUCGGUCUCCCAGUGAGCAUCGCGGGGCUUCCAUCUCACAAGGAUUUCCAGGUGGCGGAGGUGGCUGUGGGAGAUCUCAUCCUCUCGUCUUCCCUUUCAGUAAUGCCACCAACUGCCAGGGGCGCCAUCCUGGACACCUUGCCCGCCUUCUGUCCCUCACGCCCUACACCCAGGACAUCUUACGUGCACUCCUUCCUACCCCCUCCCCUAGUGCUUCUGGACCCCGCUAGUUCACUCACUCUGCAUUGCAAAACCUUCCGCUUCAGCCGUGAUCCCAGCACUCAUCGUCUGUUGUGAGCAUAUAGCUAUUGCUUCUGUACUUAGGCGGUGUUUGCUUCUCCCACUAGAGGGAAACUCUGCCUGAGGGAUCUAUCACCAAGGUAUUCAUUGUUGGGCUCAUAGCAGUGGGCCAGUAGCUCUUUCUCUCUCUAACAUUUACUUUUUUUUAAAUUGAGAUAUAAUUGAUAUAACAUAAAAUUUACCAUCUUAAAGUGUACAUGUCAGUGCAUUCCAGUACAUUCACAGAGUUGUGCCAUCAUCAUCAACGUCUAAUUCCAGAAUGUUUUCAUCACUCCCAAAAGAAGCCCCAUGCUCAUGAGCAGUCAGUAGCUCUUUCUGAAAAAAAGAAUGCUGUCCAGCUGGGAUGUGAGGAGAAGGGCUCGUAUUCCUGAUCUGGAGCUUGGAGCACACACCUGGGGGAGCGCUGCAUCUCCCCAAUCUCAAGGGACUUUUUCAGUCCCUCCUUCCUCACCACUCAAGCCCAGGGUUUAUUCUGAGGGCUCAUUGGUUAGGCUCCACUGUGUAGUGAGCUAGUGUCGUCUGGACAGAGAUAAUGAGCGCUUUCACCAGCUGCAUGCAGACAGUUCAGUCCGGGGAGCUUGGGGCUGUGGUGGCUGCAAUUUCCUAAUGGCUUCCUGAUGAGGCAGAGCCAUUUAUUAGCAGCGGAUGAGGGCUGCACAUCCCAGUCUCUCCCUUUCUCACCUACCCAGGCAGAUGGAGAGUGGCUUAAGCUCCCUCCGCCUUUUGCAUUGAUCACUUUUUGUCUGCUCGCCACCCAUUGGUUGGUCUCGCCCAUUGAUCUGGAGAUUGGGUCUGCCUGGCGACUUACCACCCUCUUGGGCUUGCUACUGGGAGAGGCGUCUGAGGCUGUCUGCCCUGGGUCCGUGUGGGCGAGACUCUGGGGCAGCAGCAGGAACAAUAGAAUGCUGAAGAUUGGGUGUUUGGGGCCAUUAAAGAGAAGCCCAUUGGGAAGGAGAAGAAAAAAAUCUGUGGGGUCUAGAAGAGAUCACAAUGAGGUGGAUCUUUCCUGGAACCCUUAGGUCUCUGCAUUCCGACUGCAUUUGCCUUCACAACUAGAGCUGCUUGUGUUACUUCAGGCCAUGGCCUUUCUGGGGGUCAACAGAUAGCUUCAUUAAUUAGAUAGAUCAGAUUCAACUUACUGGCCAGUGCCCCUGAUAUUAAGUUCUGGCUUUGUCAGUGGGGUUUGUUGUAUUCCCUCAACCCUAUCACCAUGGCUCAGUGACCCUAUUUGGAAUACCAGCAGGACUAGAAGGGUAGUGGUGUAAAACCUUUAAAUGAUAUGAGGCACUCUGCCUUUCAGUGCUUUUUAGAUAAAGGUUCAUAGAUCACUGAAGUUAACUGCAGUCUUCACUCUUUCUGGAUUGACAGGAAUAGCACCCUCAAAUUUCAGAGCCAUCAGACACCAUGGUAUCAUGCUAUCGGAGUUGACUGUUGAAAGUUGCUUAAUAUCCCUGGUAUGCAACAAGGAUCUUUGCUAGGAGGAAGCUUUUCCACCUUAGAGUCUGACCAUUGGUAUUCCAGACUUAUAACCUGAAAUAGGAGUGGAUAGCAUCAUGAAUCUGUAAAAUCCCAUCAUAUUUAUUAGAUCUUUGGAUGGCUCAUUCCUCUGUGAUUCUUAAUAACUUGGGGAGGAGUAGUGUUUAUCCAGAAUGAUGAACCAGGACUUGAUAGUAGUGAAGAUAUAGGAGAAAGCCUCUCCCUCCCAGUCCACUGUUGUAAGUAAACAGCAAUGAUGUAGAGGAAAAAAAAAUCCUGAGAGGGAGCCAGAGUUCUAGAAUUAGUAACCAGUGACUUAAGGCAAGUUGAUGUCACCUUGAGCUUCAUUUUACCCACCAGUAAAAGAAAAGGUUUGAACUAGAUGACAUCGAAAGCGUCUUCUAAUUCUGUAUUCCAGGAAUAGUGUAAGACCCCUGACCAGUGGCAGAGCUUGGCUCCUCCUUCUCUCCACUUUUCAUCCAUUUUAUAACUAUGUCUGGUUGCAAGGAAAGAGAACAUCCCUCCAAGGAGUUGUUAAAGUUUUAUAGCAAAUUCUGUAAAUUCCUCUUUUCUGCUUUUUGGUCCUGGAUAAGGCUUUAUGCAUCCUAUAGCUAUAGUGAGGGCGGGAUAGAGGGACAGAGGCAGGGAAAUGUGUGAACACACCAGGAGAGGACUCGGGCUGAUAGUUAUUGCUCCAGGCCAUAAAAAAGGCCAAAGCCAAAGAGAUAUAGAGGCCAAAAUUAUAGAUUAGGUAGGUCUACACAAACCUUGGAGUAGGCUCGUAUGAUAGGUUUAGCAGUGAGCGUAAUGGUUUAGGGAGCAUAAGCAUGCUCCCUUCAAAGCUUAUCUCUCUAGGCCCCUCCUUUUUAGUGCAGGAAACUUGAGCUGGGUCCCCACAAUUAUUGCCUAAAUCCCCGAAGUCUCAGGAUUUCUGACUCCUCAUUAGGGACAUAUAUUUAGAUUUACUGCACUGUGUGGGGCCUGAAUUCCAUUAGAUGUGCCAUGUUGGGGCGGCACCAUCGGUUUUUGGUGUGUUUAGCUGGCGUGCUGGUAUUUUUUGGAGCCUGUGAUAGGCAGAGGGACGGCCAUCUCAUGUGCUUACCAACAUGCUCAGGGUGGGGAUUUCUGCAUCUUCUCUGAUGUCAGCCUUGCUUUAGGGUAAGAAUGUGUGUCUCUCUGCCUUCUCCUGACUCCUACCAUGUGGUUCCCAUGUGGCUCUUGUGAAUUACACUGGGAUGAUUCAGCAGGGCCCUUAGAGAAGGGAAUAAUUAGUCUGUUGGGAGCAGGGGAUAGGGGAGGAGUCAAGGAAGCAGUGUUUGAAUGAAGUACCGUACCAGGUCAGGUGACCUAUAGAUCACUCACUUAGAUCUUCACAGUUUGGUCUAUUUUAGGUGGUCCAAUGUUUCAUCUGAAUUUCAGUCUCCACCAUUUGCAUAGCAUGAAAGAUGUACUAGUAUGUUUGCUUGUUAUGGGCUUGUGCACAUUAUCUGUUGUCCUGGUAGUUCAAGUUUAUGAGCGCACCCUCCAGAUGGUCUGGACCCUGAGCAUCUUGACACACUUAUGAAGUUGAUGAAGAGCAUGUGGGGCUGGGGAAGGAACGUGAUGCAUCCCUUUUAACCAUUUCUUGGCUCCUAGGGUUCGUUGGCCCUAGCAGUAUCCAGCAUGUGCCUGCUCUGUGCUUAAAAUUUUAAGUUAUAAAACAUUUAACUGUUUGCUACUAGUUCCCUCCCAAUGGGUUGACAUUAUCUGGGAUGUUGUCUGUAAAAUAUUUUAAGCUAUUUAAAGGAAAAAGAGAAAAAAAAUCUUAUUUAGAUUUGUAUAUCUCCUUACAUGUUGGUUUUCCAGGAACAAGGUGGGAAGUUAGUGACAGGAACUUGAGGCAUGAGUGGAAAUCUGAAGUUACUGCUCAGGGGAUCUCUUUGUUGAGCCCUGAAUUUCUUGCCUCUGGGAGAUUCCAGCUUUGCACGUGGGAUUCUUAAGGCUAUAAGGUUGGACUGGAUCCAGAGGGUGCAGUUGCUUACUGUUGGUUGCGCAUUAAUGCUAAGGGCUGUCGGUGGAAACUCACAAUGAAGGCAUGCAGGAGGAGAUGCCUGCAGGGGCUCACGGCCUGUGCCUCCCUCCCUGUUCCUUCCUCCCCAGCCCAGGCUCUCCUCAUGUUCAGUUUGGUGUCUGUCACAGGCUAAUCUACUGGUGGCUCUUUUUAGUAAGGCUGUAGGAGGAUUAAGGAUACAAGUAACACAGUUUGGGAAGGAUUAAAAUUGAGUAUCUCUCCAAAGCCAUGUUAGAGCAAAAGAUGAAAUUCCAGAAAAUAGAGAUACCAUCAAAAAGGGGCUGAAAUAAAGGGAAGAAGAGAUUGUCCCUGAGAUGUAAUGCAUACAUAUCUGUGAAUUUCAGCUCUUGGCCUCUUUAUUUGUCUCCAAAGAAAUGAGGAGGGAACUUUCCCAGGGAAAAGCUCCUUUAUAGUGCUCCUAAACAUGUAUAAUUAACAGACCUAAUAAGACUGUUGUUUCAGAAACCAUAGAGUUGACCUCCAUCGAUUGGUUAUUUUUUCCUUGGCGUUCCCACCUUCCUGCAACCUCUGUACAGAGAGGCCUUAAUUGCUUUGGGCUGGGCAGAGCAGCAGUUACUUUUCUCAUCUCUCCCUUCUCAGCAGUGGCUGUAUUUUAGCAGAAGGCAAGCAAGCUUAAGAGAACCUCUAGGCUAAGAAGCAACUAUACGAAGAAAAAAGAAGCCCAUUUCUAAGCAGGCAGCCUUCUUGGUGACCUCAUCUUCCUCCCAACUUGGGUCCAGUUGGAGCUGUGCAUACAGGGCAGACUUCCAGUUCCUCCUGUCUGGGACUAACAGUGGCAGAUAUAAAUAGACCAAGACUUUGUCUGUAGCCAUUGUUCUCUAACUGCCCAUUGUUUCUAGAAGCAAAGCAAUGCUGUGGCUGCAGCUCUCUUUCUCUCUCUCUCUCUCUCUCCACCCCACCCCCUUUCUCUGUCUUUCUUUAUUUCACUGUACAGGGGUCUGAAUUCCAGCUCAACCAUUUGUACUAUCAGCCACCUUUCACUUGCCAGAUGCUUAGAAACUCGAGGGGAGAACUGGCUCCACAAGUGGGAGACCAACUGAAUAUUGUAACCUCAUAUUUUGAUUCCAGUAAUGCUUUUGUCUGAGUCUUUCCAUGAUAUAUUUGUGGUCAAGACAAAGAUAUGUGGAUCUAAUGAUAGUAAAGUCAGGAGGAUUUGUAACUGGUUGAGCAACUAUACCCAACGGGUCUUGAUUAAUGUGUCAGUGUCAGAGUAAUGCAUGGUCUCUGAUGUUAUGUUAUGGGGAUCAGUACUUGCUGGUUGCCUUUUCAACAUUUUUAUUAGGGGCUUAGAAUAGAGAAAGACACAGAAAGCACACUUAGUGCAUUGCAGAUGGUGCAAAGCUGAGAAUGAUGGCUAAUAGGAUGAGCACAGAUUCAAGGUAUAAAAAAGUUCUUAGAAACAUGGAUCGAAACAAAGUGAAGUUAAUAUGGAUAAAUGUGAAGCCCUGUUGUGAAGUUAAUAAAAUUCAGUCAAUAGGUACAGAACUGGUUCAGUAUCACUUUCUAUGGAGAGGUCCUGGCAAUGUCCUUUGAGUGGCUUUUGUAGUUAGGCUGUUAGAUCAGUGUUGUCUUAGUCUGCACCAGUCAAAGCUUAUGGAGUAAGAUGAUCAUCUCAUUGUUCCCAUUUAACUUCUGAGAAGCACGAUGUUCACCUAUGAAUGCUUGUGAUGCUCUUCAGGAACAUAGGCUUAGAGGAAUGCUUCUAGGUGGAGCGAGGGGAGUGGCCAAAAACCAUGCCAACAUGAAUGGUUGAAGGAACCACGGAGUUUGGAAACCUGGACGGAAGUGAUGAUAGGAGGAAGAAAGCAGGGGAAAAGCUGCCAGAUAAGGACAAAUUUGCUUUGUGCUGCUGAUCUCUCAACAAGCAAAGCAAGGGCCUAUUGAUAGAAUUCAUAAGAAGGCAGAUUUAAACUCGUUGUGUCUAAUCAUUUUUAAAUAAUCAUUUUGGCUUAUAAGUGAAAUUGUGUAGCUCAAAAAGGAUGGGGCAACCAAAUGUCUUAAGUGAGAAGACUUCUGGGGAAGUAUGGUGGUCGUUCUUCAGGUCCUGCCCUGCCCCUCAUGACCACUCAUCAUCAAGUACUCCUCUGUGGAUCUGGAAGCUGGAGCAGGGUGUGCACGCAUACUGUGUUGCUUCAGUGCCUGUGGCUGCCAAUAUUGAGAAUCCUUGUCUGAUGUACUGGGAAAAUGGACUUGCGUAUUCUUAUUUUUCAUUGUGGUUUCCCUGGGUUGAAAACAGACAGUUGCACUGUGUGAAUGUGUAUGAGUAUGCUUUUUCCUUCUCAGUCCAGAUUUAUUUAUUAAAAGAAAAACACAUCUGCAUAAAAAAGCCUUAGAACGCAGGAAGAAUGUCCACUUUGUUUUUCUUUCUGUAGCACCGAGACAUGUGGGGUUUCAGCUUCCUCUAAGAAGUUUUUGAAGACUGGCUUUCAUCUCAAACAAGACUUUUUCCCAUUGGAAAAACGGUCCUUUUUUGGUUUAAAAAUGUAUUUAUAUAAUGUAUAAAUAAAUAAGAAAGUUGAGAGAGAAUUUCCUUUCAAAAUUGAUGAAAAAAUGUUGCUUUCUGAACAUCAUUAAUUGGGAGUCGGUUGUUGCCUCUUCCCAGGCCAUUGCCACUCUGCAUUCUGUUUCUUUGUUCUGGUUUACAAUUUUCCAAUAUUCCCUUUCUCUGCUUCCUGCUUUCUUCCCUCUCUCCUCCCUUCUUGGCCAGCUCUCCUCCUCUGUCUGAUCCCAGCUCCAGCCUUCUCCCUUGGCGGCUACCCCCAUGGCCACUGCACCACCUUCCUAGCCCCCGUUCCUCCUUCCUUUCUCUAAGCCUUUCUUCCUUCUGCCCUUCCCGGGCUAACUUUGAACAACUGAAGCCCUCACUGGAAGAGGCCUGUCUCUGUGUUUGUUUCCUGCGUGGGAGGGAGAGGCAGGCCUUGAGAAAACAGUUCAAAAGUGCAGAAAAACUUUACCUCUUCCAGCCUAAAUAAACGGGCUCUACUCCAUUUGUUUGCCCAGAUUUUUCAUUUGCCCAUGGAGAAAACUCCUCAUCGUACACCUUGCCCAGCCUGGCCUUCUUGGUGAUUCUCAGCACCACUCUCCCGAUGCCUGUUUUACCCCCCGACCAAGUGCCAAGUGGGCCCCGAGCCGAGGUUUGACCAGGCCAGUUCUGGGUAGGACGUGCAAUGGAGCCUGCUGUCGGUAGAGAGUCUCGGGGAUUGAGGUUCUUCCCUGCUACAGAAAGAGCUUUUUCUAGAAUGAAAAUGUUGGAGAAAAUGAAAAAAGAAAUGUUAUCAUGCCCCAUCAUUUUUGCCUCAUUUGCUUUUAAUUCUGUGAAUAGGUGCAGGGAGAAAACACGUGGCUUGCGUGUCUGAAGAUGUGGGAUUGAAUCCUUGUUAUAUCACUUUACUGGUUUGAUAAUCUUAGUUAAGUCACUUAAGAAACAUUUGUGAGCCUCAGUUUCCUCACCUACAUGAUAAAGAUAAUAACUACAAGUGCUUGUUUUGAAAAAUCAUAUGAGAAUAUUCAAGAAAAUGCUUUCUAAAAGAUACAGUUCUAGUCAAAUAGCAGGAAUGAUAAUUAUAGGUGGGAGUUAAGUGAAAUUAAAAUAAAUUGGUUAGCCCAAUUCAUCAGCAUCUGCAAGAUCUCAGAGGAUGAGGCCUCAAAGGCUAUUAUGUAAACCAGAAUUAGUGGAAGCUGGGAUUAUAGCAAGAUGUAGUUGUCAGAUAUUCUCCAUUGUCUUCCUGGAUGGGGUUAUCCUAUGUCAUGUUGGUACCAAAAGCCGUAUGAUCCUGUCAUGAGAAUUUUAGUGAAGGCAGGGCAGGAGUUUUCCUCAUUCAGAAGUGUAAGAUGUGGGAAGAACCAAUAGGAUGCAAUGUGGUUCUCUGCAAAGCCAUGGAGACGAAAGAGCCCAACUCAUUCUUUCCUCCUGAGUAAUGUAGAGACCAUGGCUCUGUGUUUUUCAGAUAAAGAAGUCACACUGUUCUGGGACAUUUAGGAACUAUAAAGUAUGUCAUGUGGUGGGAGUCAGGUGUAAUUAUCUAUGCAGGAAAUGCUUUGAAACAUGUGAAGUACUUUGUAAAUGGCUUGAAAUGAUCAUUUAAGAAGCUUAAAUGAUUCUUUAAUGUACCCUAUGGAGGUGGUCCUUGCACACAGGAAUCAUAAUCUCAAUAGCUAAAACUUCCUUUUAAAUUGCUUGAGUGUCGUUAAUUUAGAGGCCCAUAAAUGACAAUUAAAACGCAGCUUGGGUUUUGGCAGAUUCCAAACACAUAGAAAAGAGUUCUUAGCAUAAAAUUAUACUUUUGCUUUGUGCCAUAUUGAUUCUAAAGUGGAACUCUUAGGACGUUUUUGCAACCAAAAGGCAUCUUAGGUGCAUUGGAUUCAUGUAGUUCUGAAGUGUCACGGCAAACAUAUUUUAGAUGCUUAUUGCUGCAAAAAGUAUUUCCCGUUAGCAGAUUGGAGGAUGCAGAAUAGGUAAGAAAUUAGUCUAUUCUGUUAGAAAAAAAUGCCAGUUUCAGGGGAUGUCAAUUUCCAUUUAUAUCUCAGAAUCUGAUUUUUGCGUUUGUUUUUCUUAUUUUCUCAGUCGCUUAUUUGUACCUGGAGAAAUUGCCAGAUUCCUUCUUGAUGUUUCUGUCUGAACUCCGGCGCUGCCGAAUUACAACUGCUUUCAUUUGUUUUUCCUGCUUCCCUACCAUGUAAUGGUCAAGGGCUCAUUGGAACCAUGUGUGAGCCUGAUAUGGAAUGUGCAGAUGUCCCACUAUUAACUCCAAGCAGCAAAGAAAUGAUGUCUCAAGCAUUAAAAGCUACUUUCAGUGGUUUCACUAAAGAACAGCAACGACUGGGGAUCCCAAAAGACCCCCGGCAGUGGACAGAAACCCAUGUUCGGGACUGGGUGAUGUGGGCUGUGAAUGAAUUCAGCCUGAAAGGUGUAGACUUCCAGAAGUUCUGUAUGAAUGGAGCAGCCCUCUGCGCCCUGGGUAAAGACUGCUUUCUCGAGCUGGCCCCAGACUUUGUUGGGGACAUCUUAUGGGAACAUCUAGAGAUCCUGCAGAAAGAGGAUGUGAAACCAUAUCAAGUUAAUGGAGUCAACCCAGCCUAUCCAGAAUCCCGCUAUACCUCGGAUUACUUCAUUAGCUAUGGUAUUGAGCAUGCCCAGUGUGUUCCACCAUCGGAGUUCUCAGAGCCCAGCUUCAUCACAGAGUCCUAUCAGACGCUCCAUCCCAUCAGCUCGGAAGAGCUCCUCUCCCUCAAGUAUGAGAAUGACUACCCCUCGGUCAUUCUCCGAGACCCUCUCCAGACAGACACCUUGCAGAAUGACUACUUUGCUAUCAAACAAGAAGUCGUCACCCCAGACAACAUGUGCAUGGGGAGGACCAGUCGUGGUAAACUCGGGGGCCAGGACUCUUUUGAAAGCAUAGAGAGCUACGAUAGUUGUGAUCGCCUCACCCAGUCCUGGAGCAGCCAGUCAUCUUUCAACAGCCUGCAGCGUGUUCCCUCCUAUGACAGCUUCGACUCAGAGGACUAUCCGGCUGCCCUGCCCAACCACAAGCCCAAGGGCACCUUCAAGGACUAUGUGCGGGACCGUGCUGACCUCAAUAAGGACAAGCCUGUCAUUCCUGCUGCUGCCCUAGCUGGCUACACAGGCAGUGGACCAAUCCAGCUAUGGCAGUUUCUUCUGGAAUUACUCACUGAUAAAUCCUGUCAGUCUUUUAUCAGCUGGACAGGAGAUGGCUGGGAAUUCAAACUUUCUGACCCAGAUGAGGUGGCCAGGAGAUGGGGAAAGAGGAAAAACAAACCUAAGAUGAAUUAUGAGAAACUGAGCCGUGGCCUACGCUACUAUUACGACAAAAACAUCAUCCACAAGACAGCGGGGAAACGCUACGUGUACCGCUUUGUGUGUGACCUGCAGAGCCUGCUGGGGUACACCCCUGAGGAGCUGCACGCCAUGCUGGACGUCAAGCCAGAUGCCGACGAGUGAUGGCACUGAAGGGGCUGGGGAAACCCUGCUGAGACCUUCCAAGGACAGCCGUGUUGGUUGGACUCUGAAUUUUGAAUUGUUAUUCUAUUUUUUAUUUUCCAGAACUCAUUUUUUACCUUCAGGGGUGGGAGCUAAGUCAGUUGCAGCUGUAAUCAAUUGUGCGCAGUUGGGAAAGGAAAGCCAGGACUUGUGGGGUGGGUGGGACCAGAAAUUCUUGAGCAAAUUUUCAGGAGAGGGAGAAGGGCCUUCUCAGAAGCUUGAAGGCUCUGGCUUAACAGAGAAAGAGACUAAUGUGUCCAAUCAUUUUUAAAAAUCAUCCAUGAAAAAGUGUCUUGAGUUGUGGACCCAUUAGCAAGUGACAUUGUCACAUCAGAACUCAUGAAACUGAUGUAAGGCAAUUAAUUUGCUUCUGUUUUUAGGUCUGGGAGGGCAAAAAAGAGGUGGGUGGGAUGAAACAUGUUUUGGGGGGGGAUGCACUGAAAAUCUGAGAACUAUUUACCUAUCACUCUAGUUUUGAAGCAAAGAUGGACUUCAGUGGGGAGGGGCCAAAACCGUUGUUGUGUUAAAAUUUAUUUUAUUAAAUUUUGUGCCAGUAUUUUUUUUCUUAAAAAUCGUCUUAAGCUCUAAGGUGGUCUCAGUAUUGCAAUAUCAUGUAAGUUUGUUUUUAUUUGCCGGCUGAGGAUUCUGUCACAAUGAAAGAAAACUGUUUAUAUAGACCCCAUUGGAAAAGCAAAACGCUCUCACUGAGAUCAGGGAUCCCAAAUUCAUGGGACUUAUAUAAGAAGGACAAUUAAUGCUGAUUUGGGUACAGGGGAAUUAUGUGUGUGAAUGUCAUCUACAAUUAAAAAAAAUUAGCACAUCCCUUUACUUACUUGUUAUCAGUGGAUUCUCGGGGUUUGGACUUAAUGUUGAGCUAAGAAGCAUUAAGUCUUUGAACUGAAUGUAUUUUGCAUCCCUGGUUUUGGACGACAGUAAACGUAGGAGCACUGUUGAAGUCCUGGAAGGGAGAUCGAAGGAGGAAGAUUGACUUGGUUCUUUCUUAGUCCUAUAUCUGUAGCAUAGAUGACUUGGAAUAAAAGCUGUAUGCAUGGGCAUUACCCCUCAGGUCCUAAGAAAUAAGUCCUGAAUGCAUGUCGUUCCAAACUAACACUCUGUAAUUUUUCUUUUAUGUCUUAUUUUCCAAGAGUCCUCCAUUUUUUGCACCCCCUCACCGCCAACUCUGUUAUUCAGUAGAGAGAAGUGUACGGCUUUCUGAUUGGUGAGUGAAAAAGUAACUUGAGACACGACCUAAGUUGAAGAGUUUAGACUUGCUGAGUUUUAGAAGUGAUGGAAAUUAAGAGAGCAUUUCAAUAAAAUGUGACUUGGCUGUCUUUGGAAGAGAAGUGCAAGGCUUUCCUUUGAAGAAUUUAAAUUAGUCCGGUAGGAUGUCAGGUGAGACUGUGUAUGCAAAAUGAAUGGCACAGGUGAUGCCAGGGCCUCUUGCUUGGGUCUGAUGUCUUGGCACAGGGUAAGUGAAGGUUAAUUCCAGAAGAGAGGAAUGACUUGAAGGCAAAGGAAACUAAGGAAGGAGGUUCAGUGAGGAAAAUAAGGUUGUCCAUGAGAUUUGAAUAGAUUUUUAGUUCCCCCAAGGUUUAAAUACAAACAUAGUCAAGCAAGGUAGUCAUCUUUCUGCUGGUUGUGAGGGGGAAUCUGAAAAUGGAGUUUUAGAGGAAAAGUCAACAUCUAACUAGUGAGGAAAAGUGCCUAAUACAAUUAGAAUCUCCCUCACUCUAUAGUUGCCCAGUUGAAAGGAUAAGGAGGAGGGGUGGCUUUUAUGGACUUCCAUGAGAGAAGGAAAGAAAUAUUUCAGGUAAGCUUCUCAGGGCUGGCCCUUUUUGGGAUUUGGAUGAGAAAUUGGAAGUACUAACUACUUUCUAGCAUAUCUUUAAGAAAAUUGAUUGUUAUUUACUCCCAGAUCCUCUUGCAGACCCAGAAUUAUCAGGAACAUAGCUCUGUGAUUCAUGAGUGUCCCCAUACUGAUGAAUUGGAGCAUCCAUAUGGAAAGCAAAGGCAGAAUUAUCCCAGCUGUAUUAUUUUGAUCUUUUGGAUGCAGGUGCCUUAAUGAAGCUCUCAAAAUAUUUUAGGAGCUGCUCAGGGAGUGUUGGGUGGAACUGUUUGGACUACAUUGUUUUCUCUUAGAUUAUGUGAUUUUUGUUGGGCACUGGCAAAAGGUGUGUGUGUGAAUGUGUGCAUGUGUGUGAAUGUUGUGUGUGUGUGUGUGUGUGUGUGUGUGUGUGUGUGUGUGUGUGUUUGCAGACAUGCAAAACUGCAGCUGAAAUAAUACCUUAGAUUUCUAGGUAAGUCUUUCCACAUUUCAAUAAUGGGUAAGAGUAGAACCAGGGCCGGGUAUCAAUUAUUGCUUGCUGUUUGCAACCAGGCAUAAAAUCACUUUCUCAAAUCAUCCACCGUUCCUAUUAAAUUUAUGCCGGAAACUCUCCUUCUGUGAGUAUAACUCCUGCAGUUCCUAUAGCAGAUAAGAUAUAAGAAAGUGCCUCCUAGUGCUCCUCCGCCCGCUUGUUUGCUAAAAUUCCCUUUCUCUCUAAGUCCACCAUUUUCAAGAUUUGUAGAUAGUGUAUUAGUUAAGACAGCUUUGUCGAUCUGGCCAGAUGUUUUUUCUCCUUUGUCCAAAGGCCAGAGACCAUCCCAGGAAGAGUGGUGGGUGGUUUAUACACUGGAAAUGUUGCGUUUAUGCUUUUUAAAAACACACGUUAACUUCAGAGGAAGGAUGGGCAAAUCUGGUCUAGCUGGGUGAAACCCUUAUUUUCCCAGAGAUGCCUUAACCUUUGUUGGUUUUGGCUUUAGGGUUCAGAGUCACUUUUGUUCCCUUCUCCAUUCUGGAGAGGGACUUCCCCUACAUAGAGCCCUGAUUUUUGUGGCUGUGGGGAUUGGAGGUAGCAUUCAAAGAUCAGAUGUGCUUUUCCUCACUUUGGAGAUGAACACUCUGGGUUUUACAGCAUUAACCUGCCUAACCUUCAUGGUGAGAAAUACACCAUCUCUCUUCUAGUCAUGCUGUGCAUGCCGCUUACUCUGUUGGGGUCUAUAUAAAUUUGUUGAACUCUUACCUACAUUCCAAAGAAGUUUCAAGGAACCAUAAAUAUAUGUAUACAUAUACAUAUAUAAAAUAUAUAUAUUAAAAUAAAAUUAUCAGGAAUACUGCCUCAGUUAUUGAACUUUUUUUUUUAAGAAUACUUUUUUUUUAAGCUGAGAAGUAUAGGGAUGAAAAAGAUGUUAUAUUGUGUUUGACUAUUUUCCAACUUGUAUUUUCAUAUAAUUUAUAUUUUUUAAAAGCUGAAAAUUUAGAAGCAAGAUGAAAAAAAGGAAAAGCAGGUGCUUUUUAAAAAUCAGAACUGAGGUAGCUUAGAGAUGUAGCGAUGUAAGUGUCGAUGUUUUUUUAAAAAAAAAUGCAAAAAAAUUCUUAUGGCGGAGUUUUUUGUUUGUUUAUUUUAGUAGCUGAUGCUGGCACAUCAUUUUGCUGGAGAGUUUUUUAUAUACUGUAGCCUGAUUUCAUAUUGUAUUUUAAACUGUGUGAAAUUAAAAACAAAGAAUUUCAUUCAUAA